GGGCAGCGCGCACAUCUCGGCGGGAGCGGACUGUGAACGGCGCGGGUCCACACGGUAACGCUGGGCAACGUGGGCAACGCGGCGGGCGGCGGGCUCGCGCGGCGGGAGGGGCAGCGGCGGCGCGCCCGGGCUCUACCUCCCGGGCUCUGCCUCCCGGGCUCUGCCUCUCGGGCACUUGCCUGGCUCCUGCGCGUUCCUGGGCAUCGGCUCUGCAGCUGACACACAGUAGCGGGGACACCCGACGCCGCUAGCGACAGGCGCGCGGACGGCUGGUCCCAGAGGGACGCUGCGCUUGGGGACGCCGGCGAGACUCGCCAGGAGCCAAGAGGUGAGGAAGCGACUCUGUAGCUCGGUUCCUGAGGACUGGAGAAAGGGAAGGAUGGGCUGGUUCUCUCCCAAGGCAGUCGACCCGCCUAAGGGAGCAGCCCGACUCCGCGUACCUGGCGGAAAAGUGUCCUCGCGCUCCCGGGGGACCCGAGGCGGGCGGUCCUCCAGGGCAUGCAGGCCGCCCUCGCAGGGGCUAAAGGACACCCUGCCAGUGCCUUCACUCCAGACGCCUGCCUCAGGUCGCCCCUUCGUGUUGUGAAUACGGUGUGGAGGUGGCCAGUGCAAAGAAAAACGUAAGCUCUUUUUGUGGCGGUACUUAGCAGCGGUAUUUCAAGGAAAGUGCUCAAGAGAUUGUUCCUGGAGAGAUUUGUGUACAUCAAGUCCUAGAAAAUACAAUAUUGGACCAGGUCCCGCUCUAACUGAUAACUAGAAUAGCUAGCUUUGCCUUCAAGUCCUUUAAUGCUACAGUAAUAAAUACACUAGAGCAAGAAGUCUUCUGUCGUGGCGAAUGUUAGGUGCACAGCGUAAAUUUGUGGAAGCUUUCGCCCCUCGCUCUGUAUUUAAGCCAUCAGACACUGAGUUCAGCCGACUUAACCAAUUAUUCAGUGUAAGACUCAUUUAGUGAUUAAUCAGUGUCAUUUUAAAUAGUGAGUUCCCUGAAUACCUGUUAAGUAGGAUUCACGUCUUCGAAAAGUUUUAUUUGCACGAAGGUCAUAAUUUCAGUUGCAUUAUGCAAAAUUUGCCCGUAGGUCUUUUAGAUCUCUGCAGGAUUGGUAUGUUUUCAUGUUUCUUAUACCCCCCGUAGAGGUAGGGCAGGGCCGCUGCCACAGAAUGGGCACUACUGAGGCCAAGAAUGCUUGACCCCACUAGGGAGAAUUUUUGAGAGCCUGACUUGGGAGGUGGAAGCAGGUGACCCCAUAGGUGCUUGUACAGGUGCCCAGUUGUCAUUGAGGAGAGAGGUGGACUAUCUCUAGGUUAUUGUAUGCAUCGAUGUCUUCAUAAAUACUUUUCUGAAGAAUGUCUGAUGGUGUUGUCAUCUAGACCAUCUGAUGGCACAUCUUCCCCCACAUCCACCACUCUAAAGUCUAACCAUCCUUCAAACUGUGUUUUGCUGGUGGUGUGAGGCUUUUCCUGAAACAGCCAACCUCCCCCUGCUCUGAUUUCUGCAGCAUUUUUUCUCCAGGGCCCUUUCUGCUCUCUACCUUCUGGGAGUUAUUUAUGUAGAUGUCUCAUUUUCCCUACUGAAGGCAUUUGCUGUGGCUUUCAUGGCAAAAUGCUUGCACCUAGAAGACUCUAGAGAUAAUUGUGGGCCAGUAUUAAAUCUUAAGACUUUGGUUUUACAACAUAAAUAUCUACUUUGGAGAAGGAGAUAAUAUAAUUGAAAGGAGCUAGAGGAAUGUAUAAUGUUUACCAUUAACACUAUCCUUUAUUUACAGCCCCAUGGGGGAAAUUCCCUUUAUACCCAGGAGCCAUGUCUUACCAGGAAACAGGAAUCAUUCAAACUGGAUUUUAAAAUCAUUGCAAAUCAGUGAUGGAUCAGAAGUUGCAGAGUGCAAUCCCGAGUAAAAGUCUUCAAAAAAUUUUGCUUCAGGUAACAGAGGAAGGAAAAUUGAUCUACCACCUUAAAACCCUGAUCUAGAAAAAAUAUAUAUUCAUGAUAGGAAGUUAUAACUAAGAAAAUUUAUUUGCCUCUUAAUGCUCCUGAAUGAAAGGAAUUAUCCCUUUGUUCUUUGGGAGGACUUGUGUAUCUGAGAUUGUUGUAAUAAUCAGUCAUUUUAUUAAAACCUUGACAUGAUCACCAGGGAGGAAAAAUAGAGCAAUAGUCAAAACCUGUGUGUUAGUCCAAGAUGACUUCUGAAGAAAUGACAGCUUCUGUUCUCAUACCUGUGACUCAGAGAAAAGUGGUUUCUGCCCAGUCGGCUGCAGAUGAAAGUAGUGAAAAGGUCUCAGACAUCAAUAUUUCAAAAGCACAUACUGUCAGACGAAGUGGGGAGACUUCUCAUACCAUCUCACAACUGAACAAACUUAAAGAAGAACCUUCUGGAAGCAACUUGCCAAAGAUUCUCUCAAUAGCGAGGGAGAAAAUAGUGAGUGAUGAGAACAGUAAUGAAAAAUGUUGGGAGAAAAUCAUGCCAGAUUCUGCGAAAAACCUUAACAUUAACUGCAACAACAUAUUGAGAAACCAUCAGCAUGGCCUUCCUCAGAGACAAUUUUAUGAAAUGUACAACUCUGUUGCUGAGGAAGACUUGUGUUUAGAAACUGGAAUUCCUUCUCCACUGGAAAGAAAGGUGUUCCCUGGAAUUCAACUGGAACUAGACAGACCUUCCAUGGGCAUUAGUCCUUUAGGAAAUCAGUCAGUGAUCAUAGAGACAGGCAGAGCACACCCUGACAGCAGAAGGGCAGUAUUUCAUUUUCAUUAUGAAGUUGACAGAAGAAUGUCAGACACUUUCUGUACCCUAUCAGAAAACUUAAUUUUAGACGAUUGUGGAAAUUGUGUACCACUACCUGGGGGUGAGGAGAAGCAAAAGAAAAACUAUGUGGCAUAUACCUGUAAACUGAUGGAAUUGGCCAAAAAUUGUGAUAAUAAGAAUGAGCAGCUGCAGUGUGAUCAUUGUGACACCUUGAAUGAUAAAUACUUUUGCUUUGAAGGCUCUUGUGAGAAGGUUGACAUGGUAUAUUCAGGUGAUAGCUUUUGUAGGAAAGACUUUACUGACAGUCAAGCUGCCAAGACCUUUUUGAGCCAUUUUGAGGACUUCCCUGAUAAUUGUGAUGAUGUAGAAGAAGACGCUUUUAAAAGCAAAAAGGAGCGAUCCACUUUGUUAGUCAGGAGAUUCUGUAAAAAUGACAGAGAAGUUAAGAAAUCUGUGUAUACUGGAACAAGAGCAAUUGUGAGAACUCUGCCUUCUGGCCACAUUGGGCUGACUGCAUGGAGUUACAUAGAUCAGAAGAGAAAUGGUCCCUUACUGCCUUGUGGGAGAGUAAUGGAACCCCCGUCAACAGUGGAGAUAAGGCAAGAUGGGAGCCAACGUCUGUCAGAAGCCCAGUGGUAUCCUAUCUACAAUGCAGUGAGAAGAGAAGAAACAGAAAAUACAGUUGGAUCUCUACUCCAUUUCCUCACCAAGCUCCCAGCCUCCGAGACAGCCCAUGGAAGGAUAAGCGUUGGUCCAUGCUUAAAGCAAUGUGUCCGAGACACUGUAUGUGAGUAUCGCGCCACCCUCCAAAGGACUUCAAUAUCGCAGUACAUCACCGGUUCUCUCCUAGAAGCAACCACGUCUUUGGGAGCAAGAAGUGGCCUUCUCAGUACUUUUGGAGGAUCCACUGGACGAAUGAUGCUGAAAGAACGCCAGCCAGGCCCCUCUGUGGCCAAUUCCAAUGCCCUCCCUUCAAGUUCAGCUGGGAUCAGCAAGGAGCUGAUCGAUCUGCAGCCUCUCAUCCAGUUCCCAGAGGAAGUCGCCAGCAUCCUGAUGGAGCAAGAGCAGACUAUUUACCGCAGGGUCUUGCCAGUCGACUACCUUUGCUUCUUAACACGGGACUUGGGCACUCCUGAAUGCCAGAGCUCCUUGCCCUGCCUCAAAGCAUCCAUCUCAGCGUCGAUUCUUACCACUCAGAAUGGAGAGCACAAUGCCCUUGAAGAUCUGGUGAUGAGGUUUAAUGAGGUGAGCUCCUGGGUGACAUGGCUGAUCCUCACGGCAGGCUCCAUGGAGGAGAAGCGAGAAGUCUUUUCAUAUUUGGUGCAUGUGGCCAAAUGCUGCUGGAACAUGGGCAACUACAACGCUGUCAUGGAGUUCUUGGCUGGCCUCAGGUCAAGAAAAGUUUUAAAAAUGUGGCAGUUCAUGGACCAGUCUGAUAUUGAGACCAUGAGGAGCCUGAAGGAUGCUAUGGCCCAGCAUGAGUCCUCUUGUGAGUACAGAAAGGUGGUGACACGUGCCCUGCACAUCCCUGGCUGUAAGGUGGUUCCAUUCUGUGGGGUGUUUCUGAAGGAGCUCUGUGAAGUGCUUGACGGCGCCUCCGGUCUCAUGAAGCUUUGCCCGCGGUACAAUUCCCAAGAAGAAACUUUAGAGUUUGUAGCAGAUUACAGUGGACAAGAUAAUUUCUUACAACGAGUGGGACAAAAUGGCUUAAAGAAUUCGGAGAAGGAGUCCACUGUCAACAGCAUCUUUCAGGUCAUCCGGAGCUGCAAUCGAAGUCUGGAGACAGACGAGGAGGACAGCCCCAGUGAAGGAAACAGCUCCAGGAAAAGCUCCUUGAAGGAUAAAAGCCGAUGGCAGUUUAUAAUUGGAGAUUUGUUGGAUUCAGACAAUGACAUCUUUGAGCAAUCCAAAGAAUACGACUCUCAUGGUUCAGAGGACUCACAGAAGGCCUUCGACCAUGGGACGGAGCUCAUCCCUUGGUACGUGCUGUCCAUCCAAGCCGAUGUGCACCAGUUCCUGCUGCAGGGGGCCACGGUCAUCCACUACGACCAGGACACACACCUCUCUGCCCGCUGCUUCCUCCAGCUUCAGCCCGACAAUAGCACCUUGACCUGGGUAAAGCCCACAACUGCCUCCCCAGCCAGCAGUAAAGCAAAACUUGGUGUACUUAAUAACACAGCUGAGCCUGGAAAAUUCCCACUACUGGGUAAUGCUGGAUUAAGUAGCCUGACGGAAGGGGUCUUGGAUCUUUUUGCAGUGAAGGCUGUAUACAUGGGCCACCCUGGCAUUGAUAUACACACUGUGUGUGUUCAGAACAAACUGGGUAGCAUGUUCCUGUCAGAGACUGGUGUGACAUUGCUCUAUGGGCUUCAGACCACAGACAACAGAUUAUUGCACUUCGUGGCACCAAAGCACACAGCUAAAAUGCUCUUCAGCGGAUUAUUGGAACUCACUAGAGCUGUGAGAAAGAUGAGGAAAUUCCCUGACCAAAGACAGCAGUGGCUGCGGAAACAGUACGUCAGCCUUUAUCAGGAGGAUGGACGGUAUGAAGGCCCAACUUUGGCUCACGCUGUGGAGUUGUUUGGUGGCAGACGGUGGAGUGCUCGAAACCCCAGCCCCGGAACAUCAGCAAAGAAUGCUGAGAAGCCCAAUAUGCAGAGAAACAAUACCCUGGGCAUAAGCACUACCAAGAAAAAGAAGAAAAUCCUCAUGAGGGGUGAGAGUGGAGAGGUAACUGACGAUGAGAUGGCAACCCGAAAGGCCAAGAUGCACAAAGAGUGUCGAAGCCGGAGUGGUUCUGAUCCUCAAGACAUUAAUGAACAAGAAGAAUCAGAGGUGAAUGCCAUCGCUAACCCUCCAAACCCCCUCCCUUCCAGAAGAGCCCACUCUUUGACCACAGCUGGGUCCCCCAACUUGGCUGCCGGGACGUCAUCUCCCAUCAGGCCAGUGUCCUCCCCUGUGCUGUCUUCUUCAAACAAGAGCCCAUCCAGUGCUUGGAGCAGUAGUAGCUGGCACGGGCGGAUCAAAGGCGGCAUGAAGGGAUUUCAGAGCUUCAUGGUUUCAGAUAGCAACAUGAGUUUUGUUGAAUUUGUUGAGCUGUUCAAAUCAUUCAGUGUCAGGAGCCGCAAGGACCUGAAGGAUCUGUUUGAUGUCUAUGCAGUGCCCUGCAACCGAUCUGGCUCCGAGUCAGCCCCACUCUACACCAACCUGACAAUUGAUGAAAACACCAGCGAUCUUCAGCCUGACCUAGAUCUGUUGACCAGAAAUGUCUCGGAUUUGGGGUUGUUCAUUAAGAGUAAACAGCAGCUAUCGGACAACCAGAGGCAGAUAUCUGAUGCCAUUGCUGCUGCAAGCAUUGUGACAAAUGGCACUGGGAUUGAGAGCACAUCUCUGGGCAUUUUUGGGGUGGGCAUACUUCAGCUCAACGAUUUCCUCGUGAAUUGCCAAGGAGAACACUGCACUUAUGAUGAAAUCCUCAGCAUCAUCCAGAAGUUCGAGCCUAGCAUCAGUAUGUGUCAUCAGGGACUAAUGUCAUUUGAAGGGUUUGCCAGGUUUCUGAUGGAUAAAGAAAAUUUUGCCUCAAAAAAUGAUGAGUCACAGGAGAACAUUAAAGAACUGCAGCUACCCCUCUCAUACUAUUACAUCGAAUCUUCGCACAAUACCUACCUCACGGGCCAUCAGCUCAAAGGAGAAUCCUCGGUAGAACUCUACAGCCAGGUCCUUUUGCAAGGCUGUCGAAGUGUAGAAUUGGACUGCUGGGACGGAGACGAUGGGAUGCCCAUCAUUUAUCAUGGACAUACGCUGACAACCAAGAUCCCCUUCAAGGAAGUGGUUGAAGCCAUUGAUCGCAGUGCCUUCAUCAACUCUGACCUGCCAAUCAUCAUAUCGAUUGAGAACCACUGUUCAUUGCCUCAGCAACGAAAAAUGGCAGAAAUUUUCAAGACUGUGUUUGGAGAAAAGCUGGUGACUAAAUUCUUAUUUGAGACUGAUUUCUCAGAUGAUCCAAUGCUUCCUUCACCUGACCAACUCAGAAAGAAAGUUCUUCUUAAAAACAAGAAGCUAAAAGCCCAUCAGACGCCAGUGGAUAUCUUAAAGCAAAAGGCUCAUCAGUUAGCAUCUAUGCAAGUGCAGGCUUAUAAUGGUGGGAAUGCCAACCCCCGACCUGCCAAUAAUGAGGAAGAGGAAGAUGAGGAGGACGAAUAUGAUUAUGACUAUGAAUCCCUUUCUGAUGCAGAUGUCCUUACUGCCUCCCCUGCUCCUAACGGUCAGGAAGACAACAUUCUGGAAGACAGACCUGAAAAUAAAUCAUGUAAUGACAAGCUUCAGUUUGAAUAUAAUGAAGAAAUCCCAAAGAGGAUAAAGAAAGCAGAUAACUCUGCUUGCAACAAAGGAAAGGUUUAUGAUAUGGAACUGGGAGAAGAAUUUUAUCUUGAUCAGAAUAAAAAGGAAAGCAGACAGAUUGCACCAGAGCUUUCUGACCUUGUAAUCUAUUGUCAAGCAGUAAAAUUUCCAGGACUGUCAACUCUAAAUGCAUCUGGCUCUAGCAGAGGAAAAGAAAGGAAAAGCAGGAAGUCCAUUUUUGGCAACAAUCCGGGCAGAAUGAGCCCAGGGGAGACAGCAUCAUUUAACAAAACAUCUGGAAAAAGUUCCUGUGAAGGCAUUCGACAGACCUGGGAGGAAUCUUCUUCCCCUCUCAACCCAACCACGUCCCUCAGUGCUAUCAUUAGAACUCCCAAAUGUUAUCAUAUCUCGUCGCUGAAUGAAAAUGCCGCCAAACGUCUGUGUCGCAGGUAUUCUCAGAAACUGACCCAGCACACCGCCUGUCAGCUGCUGAGAACUUACCCUGCUGCCACCCGCAUCGACUCUUCCAACCCGAACCCCCUCAUGUUCUGGCUCCAUGGGAUACAGCUUGUGGCACUCAACUACCAGACUGAUGAUCUCCCUUUACAUUUAAAUGCUGCAAUGUUUGAGGCAAAUGGUGGUUGUGGUUAUGUAUUGAAACCUCCAGUUCUGUGGGACAAGAACUGCCCCAUGUAUCAGAAGUUUUCUCCACUAGAAAGAGAUCUGGACAGCAUGGAUCCUGCAGUCUAUUCUUUAACUAUUGUCUCUGGUCAGAAUGUGUGCCCCAGUAAUAGCAUGGGAAGCCCGUGCAUUGAAGUCGACGUCCUGGGCAUGCCUCUGGACAGCUGCCAUUUCCGCACAAAGCCCAUCCAUCGAAACACCCUGAACCCCAUGUGGAACGAGCAGUUUCUGUUCCACGUUCACUUCGAAGAUCUUGUAUUUCUUCGUUUUGCAGUUGUGGAAAACAAUAGUUCAGCGGUAACUGCUCAGAGAAUCAUUCCACUGAAAGCUUUAAAACGAGGAUAUCGACAUCUUCAGCUGCGAAACCUUCACAAUGAAGUCUUGGAGAUUUCUAGUUUAUUCAUUAACAGCAGAAGGAUGGAAGAAAAUUCCUCUGGCAAUACCAUGUCAGCCUCUUCGAUGUUUAAUACAGAAGAAAGAAAAUGUUUGCAGACUCACAGAGUCACGGUGCAUGGGGUCCCAGGGCCAGAGCCCUUUACCGUUUUCACUAUUAAUGGAGGCACCAAGGCAAAGCAGCUUCUGCAGCAAAUUCUGACAAAUGAACAAGACAUCAAACCUGUUACCACAGACUAUUUUUUGAUGGAAGAAAAAUAUUUUAUAUCUAAAGAAAAGAAUGAAUGUAGGAAACAACCAUUCCAGAGAGCCAUUGGUCCAGAAGAGGAGAUCAUGCAAAUUUUAAGCAGCUGGUUUCCAGAAGAGGGAUACAUGGGCAGGAUUGUCUUAAAAACCCAGCAGGAAAACCUAGAAGAGAAAAACAUUGUUCAAGAUGACAAAGAGGUGAUCUUGAGCUCAGAGGAGGAGAGUUUCUUUGUCCAAGUGCAUGAUGUUUCUCCAGAGCAACCUCGAACAGUCAUCAAAGCACCCCGCGUCAGCACUGCACAGGAUGUCAUUCAGCAGACCUUAUGCAAAGCCAAAUAUUCCUACAGCAUCCUGAGCAACCCCAAUCCAAGCGACUAUGUGCUUUUGGAAGAGGUGGUGAAAGACACUACCAACAAGAAGACUACCACACCAAAGUCCUCUCAGCGGGUCCUUCUGGAUCAGGAGUGUGUGUUUCAAGCCCAAAGCAAGUGGAAAGGUGCAGGAAAAUUCAUCCUUAAGCUAAAGGAGCAGGUGCAGGCAUCUCGAGAAGAUAAAAAGAAAGGCAUUUCUUUCGCAAGUGAACUCAAGAAGCUCACCAAGUCAACUAAACAGCCCCGAGGACUUACAUCACCUUCUCAGCUCUUGACCUCAGAAAGUAUCCAAACCAAGGAGGAGAAACCUGUGGGUGGCUUGUCCUCCAGUGACACAAUGGAUUACCGACAGUGACUAAGGGCAGCAUGUUUAACCCAGGUGAAGAUCUUUAAGCAAGAAGUUAAAGAGUGAACAUGGUGGAAAAAAUAUAAUUAUUUUCAUCAGACUUAAACUGGAAAUUGAUGAUUUCUGAACUGAAGCCUUCACACAUGUGAGAUCCAUGCUGAGGAGAAGCAAAAUGGCACAGGGCUAGUUGCCACCAACCAAUUUACUGAUGAAUGAAGCCCAGGGGACUGCCAUUUUAUAAAUGUCAGCAGUUGGAAAAAUCGUCACGAAUUGACUUAGAGCAAGGGUCAGCAAGCUUGUCUGUAAAGGGCCAAACAGUAAAUAUUUUAGGGCUGGGGGCCAUAAAAUAUGUUGCAACCACCCAAUUCUGCCAUUGUAGUGCAAAAGCAGCCAUAGACAACACAUACAUGAACGAACGUGGCUGUAUUCCAAUAAAACUUUAUUUAUGGACACUGAAAUUGGAAUUUCAUAUAUUUUUCACAUGUCACAAAUACUCUUGUUUUGACUUUUUUUCAACCAUUUAAAAACUUAAAAACUAUUCUUAAUUCAGGGGCCAUACAAAAACAGGUGGCAGGCUAGAUUUGGCCCAAGGACCUUAAUUUGCCAACACAACUAAGAGAAGAGAACUGGGAACAAGGAGCACAAAGAUCUGAAAACAGGAAAGGAAGUUUAGCCAUACAUUUUAUGGCCGAGAAUUAGAAGCUUAGAAUUAGAAGCUUUGGGGCAUUUCAAGUGUAAAUAUGUCCUAUAACAUAAGAGUCAUUAAAAUUCAAUUUAGUUCCUGUAUUGUGUACCACAGUGCACUCCUCUUUAGGAUUUUUUUACAUAUAGAAAUAAUAUUGGGUUUUUUUUAAGGUUAUUGCCUAUUCAGUUAAUAGGGUUGCUUUAAAAAAGGUUAUUGCUUAAUCAUAGAUUAGAUUACUCAUUUUUGGUUUUCAAAAUGAAUUUAGAAUGACGUAUAAUUUAAUAUCUACUGAAUUGCAAUGUCUUAACAAGAAACCUAACAAUUUUUUAAAGCAAAAGUAGAUUGAGUUGGCGUUUAAAUUUAUUUUGCAAGGUUUGUACUGACACUAUACUUAUAUAUUUAUUAUACAUCGCUCUCUUGAUAUUGCCAUGGAUUAGAAGCAUUAGUUCUCAGUACUUGAAGACAAACUUCUAAAAAGAAAAUAUAUGCUCUGAACAUCUGAAAUGGGCUAGACUUUCAAGUAAAAUUGCUUCAUUUCUCAUUAACUGAAGAGCUAUUGAUCCAAGUCAUACUUGCCAUUUAAUGUAAAUUAUUUUUAAACUUUGCUGUACAAAACCAUUAAGUGUAAAGGAUUCUUCAUAUUCUUAGUAUGAAGCAAAUUAUGAAUUUUAAAAAUGAAAUAUGUAUUCCUCUAAAACCCAAACUUUUAUCUUUCCAUUGGUAUCUUUGAAUUUUAAGACACUUUUCUUCAAAUUACAAAACACUAAAACUCACUCCUAAACUUCACUUUGAGAAACUUUUUUAACCAAUUAUAAAAAUAAAACCAUCCCCAUGUGUUUCUUGCAUAUUCUAAAAACAGAAGUGUUAAAAAUACACCACACAGGCUGGGCAGAGUGGCUCACGCCUGUAACUCCAGCACUUUGGGAGGCCAAGAUGGGCGGAUCAGGACAGAGAAUGAGGCCAUCCUGGCCAACAUGGUGAAACCCAAUCUCUACUAAAAGUACAAAAAUUAGCUGAGCGUGGUGGCACGUGCCUGUAAUCCCAGCUACUCGGGAGGCUGAGGCAGGAGAAUCACUUGAACCUGGGAGGUGGAGGCUGCAGUGAGCCAAGAUCGCACCACCACGCUCCAGCCUGGUGACAGAGCGAGACUCCGUCUCAAAAAAAAAAAAAAAAAAAAAAAAAAAAAAAAAAACACCAUACAGCUUUCAUGUCAUUGAAAGUUCUUACUGGGUCAAAGCCUUAAGGCUAGAACUACCAUUUUCUUGUCAACAGAAUUCAGGCUAUUCCAGUUUGAUGUAAUCUAUACAGUAGUACAGUUUUAAGUCAAAUAUUCAUUCUAACAAAUGCACAAUGCUGCUCCAUUUUAAAAAUAUUCCGGAAACACUUUAUCAAGCCUCUAUAAGUGAACAUGCCAAACAGUUUGCCCUACCACGUGUUGAAAACUGAGUUGCUGGUCUAAGUGGCUAGAGGCCAAAUGAAAACUGUGCAGAGUAACAAGAUGAAAAGACUCGUCUCUUUAGGUUUAUCACAUUUGAUUCUGAUGCUAAGCGCUGCCCCACUCCUCCUCCAUGACCUUUAACACAGGUGUAUGUUUUACAACAUAAAUCUGAGACUGAAGUUGAGACCAGGUUGUUUAGCAAGUGAGAGAAUCCAGCCUACUGCCUAGGUUGCAUCCCAAUUUAGUUGUUUAUCACAUUUUGAGGUGAAAGUACAUACUUCAUUGUAUUUGAGUCUUUGGGAUUACAGAAAGAACACAUUGUUUCAAAAUGUAAAGAGUUGGCUGGGCACAGUGGCUCAUGCCUGUAAUCCCAACACUCUGGGAGGCUGAGGUGGGUGGAUCACCUGAGGUCUGGAGUUCGAGGCCAACAUGGUGAAACCCGUCUCUACUAAAAAUACAAAAAUUAGCUGGGUACUAAAAAUACAAAAAUUAGUGGUGGUGGGCACCUGUAAAUCCCAGCUAUUGGGGAGGCUGAGGCAGGAGAGAAUUGCCUGAACUCAAGACGCAGAGGUUGCAGUGAGUGGAGACUGUGCCACUGCACUCCAGCCUGGGUACAAGAGUGAGACUCCAUCUCAAAAAAAAAAAAAAAAAGUAAAGAGUCUAGUCUACUAUUAUACACAAAUGGCCAGCACAAUCUGAUGUUGGCUGAAAAUAUUUAAGUUUUAUUUAAAGCUUUCUGAAUUAAACAGCUAUAUUAUGCCAAGUGAAAGAAAUUAUCCUAAAUAGCCACUAUGACUAUACCCAUUACCAUUUCACACUUUUUAGGCCACCAGAAAUCUGGGUAGCAAACUCUUCUCAUUAAAGUUGAUGUGGACAAGAAUCUAAAUAUGCAAGUUGGGGUCAUUACAAAAUUUUAAGAAGCAUCACUGAAAGUGAAGAGAAAGGAGCAUGAAUUCUGUCACUCUAUUCAGUGAUGCCAAAUCUGUAGGAAUGAUCCUAUCUGGGUAGAAAGUGCCCUUUGAGGGGUAAAGCUUCUUUUCAUGUCAUCAUUAGCAAGUAAAAGUUAUUUACAAAUUCUCCAGUUGGGAGUCAAUAUGAAGUCUAGACUCAACAAAAGUUGAGUUACAAGUGACUUGUUUUUAAUCAAACUUGCUUUCUUUUAUGGGAGGCUUUUAUGCCUCCCAUCUCAAUACCUCUGGAGACACUGGAAGCUCAUUAAUGAAAGUGGGCCCUCUAUGAUAUGUAUCAAUUUACCUUUUGCUAACUACAUCGUCCCCUUCCUUUCUUCUCUCCUCUUCCAAUAUCUCUAUAGACUUCUGUCCUCUGCCCAGAGACCCACAGGCCUUGCUUAAUUCUGGAAAGUUAUCAGGGCUUGCUUACUGGCCCAAUAAAAUUGAAUUAACUCUAAAACACAAAACUCCACAUCUAUGCUCCCAUGCUAGUAAAGAAGAGUAGGAUUUUCCUGGCUGGUGUCUUUGAUCUUACAUUGGCAGCCUGCAGGGAAAGUGCUCUCAUGGUGAAAGUCUCUGACCCCUUUUCAGUUGCUUAUAUAUCAGCAGUGAGGCCAGAAAAGAUAUACCUGGGACCCCAAAAAAGUUAGAGAGAAAAGGGAGAUUGUCUCUUAUACAGAGUCUAGACUUGGGUCAAUAUUCCCCAUGAUCCAUUGUUAAUAAUUUAUGUGUUCUCUGCCAUCCUUAUGUAGCAGCUUCCUAAAAGCAAUCCUUGGCUGAUGGCUAUGGAUUCUGACAUAGGAAUACCUGAAAUGAGUCCCUUUGAAACACAUACUGAGUCUCUAUGAUUACCAAGUUAUUCUUUUUUUUUUUUUUUUUUUUGAGGCAAAGUCUCACUCUGUUGCCCAGCCUGGAGUGCAGUGGUACGAUCUCGACUCACCACAACCUCCACCUCCCAGGUUCAAGUGAUUCUCCUGCCUCAGCCUCCCAAGUAGCUGGGACUACAGGUGUGCGCCAUGUCCGUCUAAUUUUUUUUAUUUUCAGUAGAGACGGGGGUUUCACUAUGUUGGUAAGGCUGGUCUCGAACUCCUGACCUCGUGAUCCACCCGCCUCAGCCUCCCAAAGUGCUGGGAUUACAGGCGUGAGCCACCACACCUGGCCUACCUACUCUUAUACAUCUCUUAGAUUCAAAACAUACUAUGCACAAGCCUGUCACCAAACAGAUCUCUGAAACCUUCCCUAUUGCAGAUGACAUAGGUCUCUAAACUUUUGACACAAGUAAUUCUAACACUGAAUUGGGUACUGUCGCAUUUUUCAAAAGCGUUAUGUGGAUGAUUUGACUCAGCAUGGAAGACUGAGGUUGUCUUACACCCAUUAUUUCCCACCCCACUCUUAAGUGCCAGCAUAGUGCUAAACACACAGUAGGUGCUCAUUAUUUGUCUAGUUAAAAAACAAAUUAAGGCUGUAGCUUAAUAUAGCCUCAGGAUAUGUGUGUGCCUGUGUGUGUGUGUGUGUGUGUGUGUGUGUGUGUGUGUGUGUGUUUAAACAUAAGCUUACAUAUAAGCGUAUGUAAGUUAAUGCACAAAUAUAUUUCCUCAAAUUCACAUAGGAUACUCAAAUAUAGAUGUAUAAUUUUGUAGUCCCACUGUGAUUCUCCAUAUGUAUAACAAGAAAAUUAAAGGCAUAAUACAGCUGUGAAAUAGCUGAUGAGUUUCUAUUUUAAGCUGAUUUUUCACCAGAAGUAUAGUUUCUGCUGCCAAAGUAAAGUAUAAAUGUAUUUGUAUAUGUGUGGAAAAUAAAUAAUUUGUGACAUGUA